CAGCCGCGCUGCGCGCACCGCGGGCUCCGGGCUCAGAAGUGCGGACGCCCGGCUCCCGGCGUGGACGCCAUGGUGCUGUGCCCGGUGAUUGGGAAGCUGCUGCACAAGCGCGUGGUGCUGGCCAGCGCCUCCCCACGCCGUCAGGAGAUCCUCAGCAACGCGGGUCUCAGGUUUGAGGUGGUCCCCUCCAAGUUUAAAGAGAAGCUGGACAAAGCCUCCUUCGCUACUCCGUAUGGGUACGCCAUGGAGACCGCCAAGCAGAAGGCCCUGGAGGUGGCCAACCGGCUGUACCAGAAAGACCUGCGGGCCCCCGACGUGGUCAUUGGAGCGGACACGAUCGUGACAGUCGGGGGGCUGAUUCUGGAGAAGCCGGUGGACAAGCAGGACGCCUACAGGAUGCUGUCCCGGUUGAGUGGGAGAGAACACAGCGUGUUCACAGGUGUCGCGAUCGUCCACUGCUCCAGCAAAGACCAUCAGCUGGACACCAGGGUCUCGGAAUUCUACGAGGAAACGAAGGUGAAGUUCUCGGAGCUGUCCGAGGAGCUGCUCUGGGAAUACGUCCACAGCGGGGAGCCCAUGGACAAAGCUGGCGGCUACGGGAUCCAGGCCCUGGGCGGCAUGCUGGUGGAGUCCGUACACGGGGACUUUCUGAACGUGGUGGGAUUCCCGCUGAACCACUUCUGCAAGCAGCUGGUGAAGCUCUACUACCCGCCCCGUCCGGAGGACCUGCGGCGGAGUGUCAAGCACGACUCCAUCCCGGCCGCGGACACCUUCGAAGACCUCAGUGACGUGGAGGGGGGCGGCUCGGAGCCCACUCAGAGGGACGCGGGCAGCCGCGAUGAGAAGGCCGAGGCGGGAGAGGCGGGACAGGCCACGGCAGAGGCUGAGUGUCACAGGACUCGGGAGACCCUGCCUCCGUUCCCGACACGCCUCCUGGAGCUGAUUGAGGGCUUUAUGCUAUCCAAGGGCCUGCUCACCGCUUGCAAACUGAAGGUGUUCGAUUUGUUAAAAGAUGAAGCACCCCAGAAGGCUGCGGAUAUUGCCAGCAAAGUGGACGCCUCUGCGUGUGGAAUGGAGAGGCUUCUGGACAUCUGUGCUGCCAUGGGGCUCCUGGAGAAGACAGAGCAAGGUUACAGUAACACAGAGACAGCGAACGUCUACCUGGCAUCGGAUGGCGAAUACUCUCUGCACGGCUUCAUCAUGCACAAUAAUGACCUCACAUGGAACCUCUUUACAUACCUGGAGUUUGCCAUCCGAGAGGGAACAAACCAGCACCACAGGGCGUUGGGGAAGAAGGCGGAAGAUCUGUUCCAGGAUGCGUACUACCAGAGCCCGGAGACGCGGCUGAGGUUCAUGCGGGCCAUGCACGGCAUGACGAAGCUGACUGCGUGCCAGGUGGCCACGGCCUUCAAUCUGUCCCGCUUCUCCUCCGCCUGCGACGUGGGAGGCUGCACGGGUGCACUGGCCCGAGAGCUGGCCCGUGAGUACCCUCGUAUGCAGGUGACUGUGUUUGACCUCCCAGACAUUAUCGAGCUGGCCGCCCACUUCCAACCCCCCGGACCGCAGGCAGUGCAGAUCCACUUCGCAGCAGGUGACUUUUUCAGGGACCCCCUCCCCAGCGCUGAGCUGUACGUCCUGUGCCGGAUCCUGCAUGACUGGCCAGACGACAAAGUCCACAAGUUACUCAGCAGGGUCGCCGAGAGCUGCAAGCCAGGGGCCGGCCUGCUGCUGGUGGAGACGCUCCUGGAUGAGGAGAAGAGGGUGGCGCAGCGCGCCCUGAUGCAGUCACUGAACAUGCUGGUGCAGACUGAAGGCAAGGAGCGGAGCCUGGGCGAGUAUCAGUGCUUGCUGGAGCUGCACGGCUUCCACCAGGUGCAGGUGGUGCACUUGGGGGGUGUCCUGGAUGCCAUCUUGGCCACCAAAGUGGCCCCCUGAAGCCCAGGCAGCAUGUUCAUUAUAGGGAUGUCCUCCCCCAGGCUGCAGGUGGACCGCCCGGUCCCCAAGUACCAUAGGACAGUCACAUAGGAGCGUGUAGUCGUGACUGAAUAAAGAAAGCAAAAGCCUG